CCCUCUUCACUUUGUACCUUUCUCUCCUCGACUGUGAAGCGGGCCGGGACCUGCCAGGCCAGACCAAACCGGACCUCGGGGGCGAUGCGGCUGCUGCCCCUGCUGCGGACUGUCCUCUGGGCCGCGUUCCUCGGCUCCCCUCUGCGCGGGGGCUCCAGCCUCCGCCACGUAGUCUACUGGAACUCCAGUAACCCCAGGUUGCUUCGAGGAGACGCCGUGGUGGAGCUGGGCCUCAACGAUUACCUAGACAUUGUCUGCCCCCACUACGAAGGCCCAGGGCCCCCUGAGGGCCCCGAGACGUUUGCUUUGUACAUGGUGGACUGGCCAGGCUAUGAGUCCUGCCAGGCAGAGGGCCCCCGGGCCUACAAGCGCUGGGUGUGCUCCCUGCCCUUUGGCCAUGUUCAAUUCUCAGAGAAGAUUCAGCGCUUCACACCCUUCUCCCUCGGCUUUGAGUUCUUACCUGGAGAGACUUACUACUACAUCUCGGUGCCCACUCCAGAGAGUUCUGGCCAGUGCUUGAGGCUCCAGGUGUCUGUCUGCUGCAAGGAGAGGAAGUCUGAGUCAGCCCAUCCUGUUGGGAGCCCUGGAGAGAGUGGCACAUCAGGGUGGCGAGGGGGGGACACUCCCAGCCCCCUCUGUCUCUUGCUAUUACUGCUGCUUCUGAUUCUUCGUCUUCUGCGAAUUCUGUGAGCCAAGCAGACCUUCCCUCUCAUCCCAAGGAGCCAGAGUCCUCCCAAGAUCCCCUGGAGGAGGAGGGAUCCCUGCUGCCUGCACUGGGGGUGCCAAUUCAGACCGACAAGAUGGAGCAUUGAUGGGGGAGAUCAGAGGGUCUGAGGUGACUCUUGCAGGAGCCUGUCCCCUCAUCACAGGCUAAAGAAGAGCAGUAGACAGCCCUGGACACUCUGAAGCAGAGGCAAGACAAACACAGGCGCUUUGCAGGCUGCUCUGAGGGUCUCAGCCCAUCCCCCAGGAGGACUGGGAUUUGGUAUGAUCAAAUCCUCAAGCCAGCUGGGGGCCCAGGCUGAAGACCUGGGGACAGGUCGAUUGCUGGACCAGGGCAAAGAAGAAGCCCUGCCAUCUGUGCCCUGUGGGCCUUUUCCCUGGGGCAGCACCUUGCCCUCCCCAGGGGAUCACUCACUUGUCUUCUAUGAAGACGGACUCUUCAUGAGGUUGAAUUUCAUGCCAGUUUGUAUUUUUAUAAGUAUCUAGACCAAACCUUCAAUAAACCACUCAUCUUUUUGUUGCCCUCCCCAA